AGUGCCCGCCGGCCGCUUCCGCUCCCGGCGCAGGCGCGGCAGCUUGGCCAGAGCGGAGGGGGCUCGGGAGAGGAGUGGACGCCGCUGGCCAGGAUGGUGCUGGAGAGCGUGGCCCGUAUCGUGAAGGUGCAGCUCCCUGCAUAUCUGAAGCGGCUCCCAGUCCCUGAAAGCAUUACCGGGUUCGCUAGGCUCACAGUUUCAGAAUGGCUUCGGUUAUUGCCUUUCCUUGGUGUACUCGCACUUCUUGGCUACCUUGCAGUUCGUCCAUUCCUCCCGAAGAAGAAACAACAGAAGGAUAGCUUGAUUAAUCUUAAAAUACAAAAGGAAAAUCCGAAAGUAGUGAAUGAAAUAAACAUUGAAGAUUUGUGUCUUACUAAAGCAGCUUAUUGUAGGUGUUGGCGUUCUAAAACGUUUCCUGCCUGCGAUGGUUCACAUAAUAAACACAAUGAAUUGACAGGAGAUAAUGUGGGUCCACUAAUACUGAAGAAGAAAGAAGUAUAAUAAUAAUAACAAUAUUUUCUCAUUCUUUGUGUAUAGAAAAUUUUAAAAUGGUGGUCUUAAUUAUUACUACUGGUUGAACAAUUAUUUCUUCCAAUUUAUUUUCUUCCUGCACUACUGUUUGUAUUUGAUCCUUUGUCUAUUCAGUCACUUAAUUAGAAAUUAAAUUGUCAAGCCUCUUAUUCUGACUUCAAAGAAUUAAUGUAUCUUCCAACAAUAAAAUCACUUCUGAUUUUAAUCUAGGAAAACCUAAAUUGUGGCUAUGGAUCCAAAGCUGUUUGUUUCUUUGAAUAUCAAUAUUUUCAACAGGAUCUUGUAUUUAAAAUUCCCACCUACAUUGUUAAAUAUGUUAUUUUUUCAUAUCUCUUUUGGUUUUGAUAAUCUGAAGUGUUUUUUUCUCGUUUUGGCCUUCCAAACUGCAUUUGGUUAGGUGAAUUAAGAAAAAUAUUGCCAUCAAGAAUUACUUGUGUUUUCACAGAGAUAGACUCUUUGCUUUAUAGAGAUUGUUGUGUAUUUAAUAUGAAUAUCCCAGCUUUAGAAAAGAAGUAAACUGGAUACAAAAAGUUCCAUUGAGGAACAGUUAUUUACAGUAUAAAAGAUUUGUUUACUUUACAAAAGGCUUGUGUCUGUGUGUGUGUGUGUGUGUGUGUGUGUGUAUUUUAAACUGACUCAGUGACAGCUGGGGUGGAAUGGCAAGAACACUUACAACCAAACUCAUGGGCUGCUGCAAUUUGAAGAUAAUUGGUAAUAAACAUAAGACAUUAAUUCAUAUUAAAAUAGUUCAGUGUUCAAAAUUGUGUUUAUGUGGAUAUUUUUCUCUUUUUAACACUAUAAACCAUUAAAAUACAGUCAUCCCUUGUAUACGCUAGGGACUGGUUCCAGGGCCACACAUAUACCAAAAUCUGCCCAUACUCAAGUCCCACAGAAAGUCUUGCAGAACCCAUAUGUAGAAAAGUUGGCCCUCCAGUUGACCCUCCGUACACAUGAGUUUCACAUCCCAUGCACAAAUGCUGAUCUGUGUGACCUCACCUGCAUUUGAUUGAAAAAAGUAUGCGCGUAAUUGUACCCACCCAGUUCAAACCCGUGUGUAAGGGUCAACUGUACAAAAAAGUUUGUGAAAUAAACGUACUGGAGAAUCUUUAAAAUUUUUGUGCUUUUUAAUCCUACUAUUAUGAAUCUUUUUAGUUUCAUCUUACAUUACUACUCUCAUAAUAGCUAUCCUUAGCCAGGUGCCAUGGCACAGGCCUGUAGUCCCAACUGCUGGGAAGAUUGAGGUGGGAGGAUGGCUGCAGUACAAGAGCCCAGGAGUUCAAGGCCAGGCUGGGCAACCUAGUGCUCCGCCUCUGCUGGGCUCUGUAGGGAAUCCUUUCUGUUGUAAAAGAGUUACCAUUUAACUCCCUUCACUGAGUGCGUUUCUGAGACCUUGCUAGGCACUCUGGAAACUGCUUAGUUGAGAAAAGACAAAUACAAAAGCUUUUCUUUAGUCUAUUUAAGAUACAGUUUAUUCAGUUCACUUUGCUUUCUUUUUAUAAGAAUGUACAAGAGGCAGACAGAGGUAAUCCUUCUAGAAAUAAAACUAAUUGUUAUUGGGCACUUGUAUGUACCAGACACUACACUAAGCAUGGUACUUGGGUUUUUAAUUUAUUACAUGUAAUGUCAGUAGGUUCAAUUAUAUGAUCGUAACAUCUUCAUGACCAGCAGCAUGUAUUUUAGAGUUAGAAAUGUAGUCUGGUUUUUGAGAAGUUUUACAAGGUGUAUGUCCAAAAUUGUUCUUUCCUCACAUGUCAGUGGGGGAUAAAUACAGCAUUGCUCUCACUUCUUUGACUCUGGGUGCUUUUUCGGAUACAUUUUCUUCAACACUGUUAAGGGGCCUCACUGUCAGAUUAACCAAUUAUUUUUCCACAGUUGGUCACCAGACUUUGGAAAAAAUCCACCUCACCAAAAUUUUGGAUAUCCUGAUCUGUGUUCAUGAAAUGCUCUUCUUUUUGUAAAAUCUAUCACUGCAUCUCACAGCAACUUGUUUUCACACAUGUUCUAGUGGUUCCCAUAACUUAGAUUUUACAGGAGGCAAAUUUACUAAAAAUGAGGAGACUAAAAUGAAUGACCAACUUUGAAUUUUGUCAAAUAACAUUGAAAAUGAAUUAUCUCAUAAAAGGUAAUUUUAAUACCCCAAAAGUAAGAUGGUUGUACUCUCAGAAUAAAGACUUUUUCCCUGCCACAUUUUCAGUUGUUAAAAUAUGCUAAGAGCUAUGCCCAUAUCUUUUCCCACCUGUGCACAUUUUUCAGAAGCGUAGGGUUGGUAGUAAGCUGUUGCUUUAAUAACUCCUUUAAAUAAGCAUUAUUAGCAGUUUGCAUUACUUCUUGUAAAUUUACACAAUUUUAUCUUGUCCAUCUUUAAAAAAUAGACAUCUAAUAACCAAAUGUAUUUGAAUUGAUGCAGUGUAAGUAACUUGUAGAACUUGAGGAUAAGUGGUAAAAGAAAAAAAAAAGUAACUUGGCUCUUGAAAUACAUGUCUUCGGUUUCUAGAGCCUUCAAAAUACAGCCCUGUUGUUACUGCGUCACAUGAUUGUUUUGAGGACUGCUUCUGCUUACCUAGGAAACUACUCAUGCCUUACUCAGCAAAUGAACAUCACUAUUACAUAAACAUCAGGUAUCCAAAAGUGUUAGCAGGCUUGAGGUAUGAAUGAUUCAUUCAUAUGGGUAAUUAAGCAAGUUGAAUUAUGGAAAGCACCUCACAAUUCACACAAUUCAGCUUUGAGUUCAAUGCCAAAUACGAUGAUUCAUUAAGUUGACUUUGUAUUUUGUAACCUAAUUUGUUAAUAAGUAAGUUACAGGAAGCCAAUUAAGCCAGCUGCUGAUCUAUAUAGUACUACCUUCCUCAUUGUGAUUCCAUAGUCUUCCAAUAGAAAUGUGCUGUCAGAAUCUGUAUAGAGAGUUUGUAAAUGCCACUAUUUAACAAGGUUCUUAAGAAUUUAGGUGGAUGUUUUAUUUGAUACCUACCAAAGAAGCCUAAGUAAUUGUAUAAUACUUAACCCAUUUAGAAUUCAGUUGUGGCAGCAUAACCAAUCUGGAGAGACCAGGGGAGAUGUUACUAAUGCUUGUACUUUAUUCAGAAAUGAGUGCCUCAUUGGCUUGGUGCAGUGACGACACACCUGUAAUCUCAGCACUUUGGGAGGCUGAGGUGGGUGGAGUACUUGAUCUCAGGAGUACCAUACCAGCUUGGGCAACGUGGUGAGAUCUCAUCUCUACAGAAAAAUGCAAAAAUUAGCCGGGCACAGUGGCGCACCAGUAGUCCCAGUUACUCGGGAGGCUGAGGCACAAGAAUCUCUUGAGUUGAGGAGGCCAAGGUUGCAGUGAGCCAAGAUUGUGCCACUGCACUCCAGCCUGGGCAACAGAAGUGAAACCCUAUCUUAAAAAAAAAAAAAGUCUUUUUUUUUUUUCAUCUAAUCAAAUUUAUUGUGGCAGAAAUCAGUACGAAGUUCGUAGGACAGGAGGAAACCAAUAUAAAUAUCUCAGCAUUGUAGGAAAUUUAACCCAUGGAAAGCAGGGGUGAAUUAAAGACCACUUUGAAGGCUGGGAAAAGCAGAUAAUUUAGAUAUAGUCAAAGUAUGAAAUCAUUGAUAGAUCCAGAACAAGGAAAUGAUGUAUGUGUUUACAUAUUACAUCUACUUUAUUAACAAUUUUCCCUCUGUUAAACUAAUAUCGACUAAUAGUAGUCUAGGUAAGUCAAGUUCAAAUUAAGUGGUAAUUGAAAAAGUCUUCUUUUUAAAAAAUUUUUAAUGGUAGAGGCAGCAGCUACCCAGAGUCUACUUAUUCUUACUUCACAUUGAAUUCUAACAAGUUUGGUUAUCUGAUUUCUGCUUCUUAACAAAUCACAAGUAUCAAAAGGGUCUUGCAGAAGGGGUGAACUACAAAAUGUGACAGCUGACAGCAAGUCAGGGGAACAAAAAUAAAUUUAAGGUGAACAUUAAAGGCAUAGCAGCUUGAGACAAUUUAUAGGAUUCUGCAUACAACUGUCUCUGAGGACAUCACUGUGAUCAAAUUAUACAAGUGAUGUUUAGUGAUGAAUUGGAAUCAAGAUAAGUAGUAUGUGUUAUUCAAAAAGGCAGGAUAUGUGUUGCAUUUGGUGGUAACAAUUUCCCCUUAGCUAUUUAGUUAAAAGCUUAGUGCUUAACAUGUUGGAAAAUUUAUAUGUAAAAUAUAUUGACUUACUCGAUGAUUGGAGGCUUUAUCACAGGAAGUUUUCCCAUUCAAUUGAAACAUUUUUCAAGCUUAAUGACUAUAAUUUACUACAUAAUUAUUUAUUUUGUUAAAGUUUGAGGAAAACUAAAUAAAGCAGUAGCAAUUUAAGUCAUAAUAAAUUUUGUUAGAUGACUUCUUCCACUUUAGGGGGAAUUAAAAAUCAUGUUUAAAAACCACAUGUGCAGCAGUUCUGUGACUCCCUCAACAUCCGGUUGGCCAUAUAGUCCCUUUGCACCACAGAGGUUGGAGUAUAGAAUAUGCCCAAAGCUGUUUUGUUUUGUUUUAACUAUGCUUCAUCAUCUGAGGUUGUGUUAACAUAGUUUGUCCUAAUAGUCUUUUACUGGAAACUUGCUAUAUUUGAUCAUGUUCAGCAAGUAAACUAAUUUUAUCUACUUUCAUAUAUUUUGAGACAAAGUCUGGCCCUGUCACCCAGGCUGGAGUGCGGGGGCAUGAUCGUAGCUCACUGCAGCCUCAGCCUCUUGUGCUCAAGCGAUCCUCCCACCUCAGCCUCCCAAGUAGCUGAGACUACAGUCAUGCUUCAUCAUGCCCGGCUAAUUUUUUAUUUUUCUAAGAGACAGAGUCUCACUGUGUUACCCAGGCUGGUCUCGAAGUCCUGGACUCAAGUGAUCCUCCCUGCCUCAGCACUCCCAAAGUGCUGGGAUUGCAGGCAUGAGCAACCAUGCCUGGUGUUUUAUCUUUUGCAGAAAUCCAAUUUAGUAAAGUCAUGUUGUAGCAAGCAUCACUUUAAUAUAAAAAGUGUACAGCUUAUAUUAUUAGCAAUUGUACUGUUUAAUUUUAUAUUAGUUAUGGUCUUGAAGGACAUUGAAAAUCUGUUCAGAAAGACUAUGUUUUUCAACCAGAGAUGACAUCACUCUAACUUUCCUUUGGUUUAAAUGCUUGAUUCUUCGCUUACAAAACUUCUGUUUUGAACAACUAUGGUGAGAAAGUAUAUUUGUGAUACUGUUUUCUUAGAACACUGUUGUCAGAUAGAUCAGCCAUAAUGUUAACACAUUUCUGAUCUCUAUUAUAAGGCUGUAAUUUUCCAAAAUAAUACAGAAAAGGAGAAAAGGGUAGUACAUUUCAUAAUUAGAGAUAACCCUGUACUAGUGAGAAAAUAAAAAUGUCAAGUUUAUUAAA